GCAGGCGCAGGCGCAGGCGAGGGGCUGGGUGGCGGUUGAGACAGCGGCGGUACUGGGAGGCGUAGGUGAGGGUCGCGAGGCUGCCCGAGCUUCUGAGCGAGCGCGGUGCUUUUGGGAACGCGGGACGGGCGAUCUGCGGCGCCAGGAGCUGGGCCGAGGCGCGGCGGCGCGGCUGCCGGCUGCCCUGUGAAUGGGAAGUUACGCGAAGUCCACCCAGCGUUUCUGAGGCAAUCUGAAGGCAAAUCCUGUUUAGACCCAGGCGAAGGUUCCCGGUGACCCGGGCUCUCACCAGCCAAUUGUCCCUUGCCGUCCUCCUGAGGGUGCCUGGAGCUUAAGCACUGUGUGCUCUUGGCCUCCACACUGGGGAUGCCGCUGACUCCCACUGUCCAGGGCUUCCAGUGGAUUCUCCGAGGCCCUGAUGUAGAAACUUCCCCAUUGGGUGCACCAAGAGCAGCCUCACAUGGUGUGGGCUGACAUCAAGAGCUGCCAGAUCCAACAGGUCCUGGGAGAGUAGGAGCCAGUGCAAGGAGAGAAGUCCAUUGAGAAAGGCAAAUGGAUGACAUCAGACCCAGGGGCUGAGGUCCCCAACUGCAGCUGGGUAGCUUCUGGAGUGGACAAGGAGCAACAGGGAAGUUCGUGGCCUGGUGUUCUGGGAUCCACUGUCUCAUCUCAUUCUUGUGGGCACCAGAACGUAUCCAAAGACAAGACUCAGUGUCUCUGGCAACAGUGAGCCAGAGAUAGAAUGUGUUUCAGAGGAGGAGGAAGGGGUUGUUGUACCCCAUGGAAACAGUAUAUUGUUUUACAGUAGCGUGUCUUUCUCUAAUAACUACUUAGCGUGUUCCUGUUAAUGGAAAAUAUUGGUGGUGUAAGUUUCCCCACUGUUCUCAUCUUCAUGUAAAUUUGUUCAUUUCCUUCCUUCCUUCCUUCCUUCCUUCCCUACUUCCCUCCAACUCUCUUUCUCUCUCUUUUUAUUCUUUCCCUCCUUCCCACCCGCCCUCCAUCCCUCCCUUCCUUCCUCCUUCCCUCCUUCCCUCCCUUCUUUCCUUUCUUCCUUUCUUCUUUUCUUCUUCUUUCUCUCUCAUGCUCUCUCUUUUUCUUUCCUUUUCAUUCUCUCUACUUUUUUGAAGAGAUCACACUGUACUGAAACCUACAUUAUUUUCCAAAAUCUCUGGAUCUGCUUCUGUCUUGCAGGCAGAGAGCUCAUCCAGUAGCCCUUAGCUCUUCCCAGCCCCCUCCUUUGAUUUGUGGGUGCCACUGCGGCAGCUGCUGAGUCUCAGUGGUUUCUAGUCUUCACCAAGUUCUGCCCACCCAGAUGGUUUUUACCUGUCCUCACCAGAAACCUGCACUGUCUAGAUUGCUGAGGCUGCUUCUCCUUAACCGAUCUGCUAUCUGUAUUCCAGGGGCACCCCAGGGUUAGAGGUAAAUGGCACAGGCCUUGAAAUCUCCAACUGCUCUGACUCCAGGAAGAUGGCCAAUCUUUCCUAAGCUGCUCACCUUACAAGAAAACGAAUCGUACUGCUAAGAAUUCAAACUUCAGCAGUCAUGGGGAGCCUUGGAAGGAGCCCGAAUCACUGAUGGAAUUGGACAGUGCAUGGAGAUGGUUCAGCAGGACAAGGUGCUGAAAACUCAUCCCCGUGUGACCUCAAAAUGUCAGGUCUCCCAGAUGCCAGAAAAUACAUUUACUUAAAGCCGUUGAUACGUCUUAAAGCGGUUUCCUUACAGUGUCAUUGGAGGACAGUGUGGAGUGCAGAGAGACAUGCUUUGAAAUGGGAUUGAUCCAGUCCUCCUUCCUUCACUACCACAUGAAUGCUGGGCAGCCCAGGGUCAACCCACCGCACCCUCAACUCAGACGGUUACCUGGCACGCUGGCCACAGUCUACCUCACUCUUAUCAGAGUCUGAGCUACUGGCAGUGCUUUCAGCUCUGAGUUCAGGCACCUCGAACCUUGUUUUUGUGGUGAAGGAUCCUAAAGUGCUGUGGGGAGUGAUCACAUUUUUCACAACAUCCCUGGCUCCACCUCUUCUGCCACAAACGUCAGCAUGGUGGUAUCAGCUGGCCCUUGGUCCAGCGAGAAGGCAGAGACGAACAUUUUAGAAAUCAACGAGAAAUUGCGCCCCCAGCUGGCAGAGAAGAAACAGCAGUUCAGAAACCUCAAAGAGAAAUGUUUUGUAACUCAACUGGCCGGCUUCCUGGCCAACCGACAGAAGAAAUACAAGUAUGAAGAGUGUAAAGACCUCAUAAAAUUUAUGCUGAGGAAUGAGCGACAGUUCAAGGAGGAGAAGCUUGCAGAGCAGCUCAAGCAAGCUGAGGAGCUCAGGCAAUAUAAAGUCCUGGUUCACUCUCAGGAACGGGAGCUGACCCAGUUAAGGGAGAAGUUACGGGAAGGGAGAGAUGCCUCCCGCUCAUUGAAUCAGCAUCUCCAGGCCCUCCUCACUCCGGAUAAGCCAGACAAGUCCCAGGGGCAGGACCUCCAAGAACAGCUGGCUGAGGGGUGUAGACUGGCACAGCAACUUUUCCAAAAGCUCAGCCCAGAAAAUGACGAAGAUGAGGAUGAAGAUGUUCAAGUUGAGGAGGCUGAGAAAGUACUGGAAUCAUCUGCCCCCAGGGAGGUGCAGAAGGCUGAAGAAAGCAAAGUCCCUGAGGACUCACUGGAGGAAUGUGCCAUCACUUGUUCAAAUAGCCACGGCCCUUGUGACUCCAACCAGCCUCACAAGAACAUCAACAUCACCUUUGAGGAAGACAAAGUCAACUCAGCUCUGGUUGUAGACAGAGAAUCCUCUCAUGAUGAAUGUCAGGAUGCUGUAAACAUUCUCCCAGUCCCUGGCCCCACCUCUUCUGCCACAAACGUCAGCAUGGUGGUAUCAGCCGGCCCUUUGUUCAGCGAGAAGGCAGAGAUGAACAUUCUAGAAAUCAACGAGAAAUUGCAUCCCCAGCUGGCAGAGAAGAAUCAGCAGUUCAGAAACCUCAAAGAGAAAUGUUUUGUAACUCAACUGGCCUGCUUCCUGGCCAACCAGCAGAACAAAUACAAAUAUGAAGAGUGCAAAGACCUCAUAAAAUCUAUGCUGAGGAAAGAGCGACAGUUCAAGGAGGAGAAGCUUGCAGAGCAGCUCAAGCAAGCUGAGGAGCUCAGGCAAUAUAAAGUCCUGGUUCACUCUCAGGAACGAGAGCUGACCCACUUAAGGGAGAAGUUACGGGAAGGGAGAGAUGCCUCCCGCUCAUUGAAUCAGCAUCUCCAGGCCCUCCUCACUCCGGAUAAGCCAGACAAGUCCCAGGGGCAGGACCUCCAAGAACAGCUGGCUGAGGGGUGUAGACUGGCACAGCAACUUUUCCAGAAGCUCAGCCCAGAAAAUGACGAAGAUGAGGAUGAAGAUGUUCAAGUUGAGGAGGCUGAGAAAGUACUGGAAUCAUCUGCCCCCAGGGAGGUGCAGAAGGCUGAAGAAAGCAAAGUCCCUGAGGACUCACUGGAGGAAUGUGCCAUCACUUGUUCAAAUAGCCACAGCCCUUGUGACUCCAACCAGCCUCACAAGAACAUCAACAUCACCUUUGAGGAAGACAAAGUCAACUCAACUCUGGUUGUAGACAGAGAAUCCUCUCAUGAUGAAUGUCAGGAUGCUGUAAACAUUCUCCCAGUCCCUGGCCCCACCUCUUCUGCCACAAACGUCAGCAUGGUGGUAUCAGCCGGCCCCUUGUCCAGCGAGAAGGCAGAGAUGAACAUUCUAGAAAUCAACGAGAAAUUGCAUCCCCAGCUGGCAGAGAAGAAACAGCAGUUCAGAAACCUCAAAGAGAAAUGUUUUGUAACUCAACUGGCCUGCUUCCUGGCCAACCAGCAGAACAAAUACAAAUAUGAAGAGUGCAAAGACCUCAUAAAAUCUAUGCUGAGGAAUGAGCGACAGUUCAAGGAGGAGAAGCUUGCAGAGCAGCUCAAGCAAGCUGAGGAGCUCAGGCAAUAUAAAGUCCUGGUUCACUCUCAGGAACGGGAGCUGACCCAGUUAAGGGAGAAGUUACGGGAAGGGAGAGAUGCCUCCCGCUCAUUGAAUCAGCAUCUCCAGGCCCUCCUCACUCCGGAUGAGCCAGACAAGUCCCAGGGGCAGGACCUCCAAGAACAGCUGGCUGAGGGGUGUAGACUGGCACAGCACCUUGUCCAAAAGCUCAGCCCAGAAAAUGACAAUGAUGACGAUGAAGAUGUUCAAGUUGAGGUGGCUGAGAAAGUGCAGGAAUCGUCUGCCCCCAGGGAGAUGCCGAAGGCUGAAGAAAAGGAAGUCCCUGAGGACUCACUGGAGGAAUGUGCCAUCACUUGUUCAAAUAGCCAUGGCCCUUAUGACUCCAACCAGCCACAUAGGAAAACCAAAAUCACAUUUGAGGAAGACAAAGUCGACUCAACUCUCAUUGGCUCAUCCUCUCAUGUUGAAUGGGAGGAUGCUGUACACAUUAUCCCAGAAAAUGAAAGUGAUGAUGAGGAAGAGGAAGAAAAAGGGCCAGUGUCUCCCAGGAAUCUGCAGGAGUCUGAAGAGGAGGAAGUCCCCCAGGAGUCCUGGGAUGAAGGUUAUUCGACUCUCUCAAUUCCUCCUGAAAUGUUGGCCUCGUACCAGUCUUACAGCGGCACAUUUCACUCAUUAGAGGAACAGCAAGUCUGCAUGGCUGUUGACAUAGGCGGACAUCGGUGGGAUCAAGUGAAAAAGGAGGACCAAGAGGCAACAGGUCCCAGGCUCAGCAGGGAGCUGCUGGAUGAGAAAGGGCCUGAAGUCUUGCAGGACUCACUGGAUAGAUGUUAUUCAACUCCUUCAGGUUAUCUUGAACUGACUGACUCAUGCCAGCCCUACAGAAGUGCCUUUUACAUAUUGGAGCAACAGCGUGUUGGCUGGGCUCUUGACAUGGAUGAAAUUGAAAAGUACCAAGAAGUGGAAGAAGACCAAGACCCAUCAUGCCCCAGGCUCAGCAGGGAGCUGCUGGAUGAGAAAGAGCCUGAAGUCUUGCAGGACUCACUGGAUAGAUGUUAUUCGACUCCUUCAGGUUAUCUUGAACUGCCUGACUUAGGCCAGCCCUACAGAAGUGCUGUUUACUCAUUGGAGGAACAGUACCUUGGCUUGGCUCUUGACGUGGACAGAAUUAAAAAGGACCAGGAAGAGGAAGAAGACCAAGGCCCACCAUGCCCCAGGCUCAGCAGGGAGCUGCUGGAGGCAGUAGAGCCUGAAGUCUUGCAGGACUCACUGGAUAGAUGUUAUUCAACUCCUUCCAGUUGUCUUGAACAGCCUGACUCCUGCCUGCCCUAUGGAAGUUCCUUUUAUGCAUUGGAGGAAAAACAUGUUGGCUUUUCUCUUGACGUGGGAGAAAUUGAAAAGAAGGGGAAGGGGAAGAAAAGAAGGGGAAGAAGAUCAACGAAGAAAAGAAGGAGAAGGGGAAGAAAAGAAGGGGAAGAAGAUCAAAACCCACCAUGCCCCAGGCUCAGCAGGGAGCUGCUGGAUGAGAAAGGGCCUGAAGUCUUGCAGGACUCACUGGAUAGAUGUUAUUCAACUCCUUCAGGUUAUCUUGAACUGACUGACUCAUGCCAGCCCUACAGAAGUGCCUUUUACAUAUUGGAGCAACAGCGUGUUGGCUGGGCUCUUGACAUGGAUGAAAUUGAAAAGUACCAAGAAGUGGAAGAAGACCAAGACCCAUCAUGCCCCAGGCUCAGCAGGGAGCUGCUGGAUGAGAAAGAGCCUGAAGUCUUGCAGGACUCACUGGAUAGAUGUUAUUCGACUCCUUCAGGUUAUCUUGAACUGCCUGACUUAGGCCAGCCCUACAGAAGUGCUGUUUACUCAUUGGAGGAACAGUACCUUGGCUUGGCUCUUGACGUGGACAGAAUUAAAAAGGACCAGGAAGAGGAAGAAGACCAAGGCCCACCAUGCCCCAGGCUCAGCAGGGAGCUGCUGGAGGCAGUAGAGCCUGAAGUCUUGCAGGACUCACUGGAUAGAUGUUAUUCAACUCCUUCCAGUUGUCUUGAACAGCCUGACUCCUGCCUGCCCUAUGGAAGUUCCUUUUAUGCAUUGGAGGAAAAACAUGUUGGCUUUUCUCUUGACGUGGGAGAAAUUGAAAAGAAGGGGAAGGGGAAGAAAAGAAGGGGAAGAAGAUCAACGAAGAAAAGAAGGAGAAGGGGAAGAAAAGAAGGGGAAGAAGAUCAAAACCCACCAUGCCCCAGGCUCAGCGGUGUGCUGAUGGAAGUGGAAGAGCCUGAAGUCUUACAGGACUCACUGGAUAGAUGUUAUUCGACUCCGUCAAUGUUCUUUGAACUACCUGACUCAUUCCAGCACUACAGAAGUGUGUUUUACUCAUUUGAGGAACAGCACAUCAGCUUCGCCCUUGACGUGGACAAUAGGUUUCUUACUUUGAUGGGAACAAGUCUCCACCUGGUCUUCCAGAUGGGAGUCAUAUUCCCACAGUAAGCAGCCCUUACUAAGCCGAGAGAUGUCAUUCCUGCAGGCAGGACCUAUAGGCACGUGAAGAUUUGAAUGAAACUAUAGUUCCAUUUGGAAGCCCAGACAUAGGAUGGGUCAGUGGGCAUGGCUCUAUUCCUAUUCUCAGACCAUGCCAGUGGCAACCUGUGCUCAGUCUGAAGACAAUGGACCCAAGUUAGGUGUGACACGUUCACAUAACUGUGCAGCACAUGCCGGGAGUGAUCAGUCAGACAUUUUAAUUUGAACCACGUAUCUCUGGGUAGCUACAAAGUUCCUCAGGGAUUUCAUUUUGCAGGCAUGUCUCUGAGCUUCUAUACCUGCUCAAGGUCAGUGUCAUCUUUGUGUUUAGCUCAUCCAAAGGUGUUACCCUGGUUUCAAUGAACCUAACCUCAUUCUUUGUAUCUUCAGUGUUGAAUUGUUUUAGCUGAUCCAUCUUUAACGCAGGAGGGAUCCUUGGCUGAGGAUUGUAUUUCAGAACCACCAACUGCUCUUGACAAUUGUUAACCCGCUAGGCUCCUUUGGUUAGAGAAGCCACAGUCCUUCAGCCUCCAAUUGGUGUCAGUACUUAGGAAGACCACAGCUAGAUGGACAAACAGCAUUGGGAGGCCUUAGCCCUGCUCCUCUCGAUUCCAUCCUGUAGAGAACAGGAGUCAGGAGCCGCUGGCAGGAGACAGCAUGUCACCCAGGACUCUGCCGGUGCAGAAUAUGAACAACGCCAUGUUCUUGCAGAAAACGCUUAGCCUGAGUUUCAUAGGAGGUAAUCACCAGACAACUGCAGAAUGUAGAACACUGAGCAGGACAACUGACCUGUCUCCUUCACAUAGUCCAUAUCACCACAAAUCACACAACAAAAAGGAGAAGAGAUAUUUUGGGUUCAAAAAAAGUAAAAAGAUAAUAUAGCUGCAUUUCUUUAGUUAUUUUGAACCCCAAAUAUUUCCUCAUCUUUUUGUUGUUGUCAUUGAUGGUGGUGACAUGGACUUGUUUAUAGAGGACAGGUCAGCUGUCUGGCUCAAUGAUCUACAUUCUGAAGUUGUCUGAAAAUGUCUUCAUGAUUAAAUUCAGCCUAAACGUUUUGCCGGGAACACUGCAGAGACAAUGCUGUGAGUUUCCAACCUUAGCCCAUCUGCGGGCAGAGAAGGUCUAGUUUGUCCAUCAGCAUUAUCAUGAUAUCAGGACUGGUUACUUGGUUAAGGAGGGGUCUAGGAGAUCUGUCCCUUUUAGAGACACCUUACUUAUAAUGAAGUAUUUGGGAGGGUGGUUUUCAAAAGUAGAAAUGUCCUGUAUUCCGAUGAUCAUCCUGUAAACAUUUUAUCAUUUAUUAAUCAUCCCUGCCUGUGUCUAUUAUUAUAUUCAUAUCUCUACGCUGGAAACUUUCUGCCUCAAUAUUUACUGUGCCUUUGUUUUUGCUAGUUUGUGUUGUUGAAAAAAAAAACAUUCUCUGCCUGAGUUUUAAUUUUUGUCCAAAGUUAUUUUAAUCUAUACAAUUAAAAGCUUUUGCCUAUCACUCU